GAGAAUCCCGGUGGUGAGCGGGGAUGGCGGUUGUAGCGGCGGCUGCCGGCUGGCUACUCAGGCUCAGGGCGGCAGGGGCUGAGGGGCACUGGCGUCGGCUUCCUGGCGCGGGGCUGGCGCGGGGCUUUUUGCACCCCGCCGCGACUGUCGAGGAUGCGGCCCAGAGGCGGCAGGUGGCUCAUUUUACUUUCCAGCCAGAUCCGGAGCCCCGGGAGUACGGGCAAACUCAGAAAAUGAAUCUUUUCCAGUCUGUAACAAGUGCCUUGGAUAACUCAUUGGCCAAAGAUCCUACUGCAGUAAUAUUUGGUGAAGAUGUUGCCUUUGGUGGAGUCUUUAGAUGCACUGUUGGCUUGCGAGACAAAUAUGGAAAAGAUAGAGUUUUUAAUACCCCAUUGUGUGAACAAGGAAUUGUUGGAUUUGGAAUCGGAAUUGCGGUCACUGGAGCUACUGCCAUUGCGGAAAUUCAGUUUGCAGAUUAUAUUUUCCCUGCAUUUGAUCAGAUUGUUAAUGAAGCUGCCAAGUAUCGCUAUCGCUCUGGGGAUCUUUUUAACUGUGGAAGCCUCACUAUCCGGUCCCCUUGGGGCUGUGUUGGUCAUGGGGCUCUCUAUCAUUCUCAGAGUCCUGAAGCAUUUUUUGCCCAUUGCCCAGGAAUCAAGGUGGUUAUACCCAGAAGCCCUUUCCAGGCCAAAGGACUUCUUUUGUCAUGCAUAGAGGAUAAAAAUCCUUGUAUAUUUUUUGAACCUAAAAUACUUUACAGGGCAGCAGCGGAAGAAGUCCCUAUAGAACCAUACAACAUCCCACUGUCCCAGGCCGAAGUCAUACAGGAAGGGAGUGAUGUUACUCUAGUUGCCUGGGGCACUCAGGUUCAUGUGAUCCGAGAGGUAGCUUCCAUGGCAAAAGAAAAGCUUGGAGUGUCUUGUGAAGUCAUUGAUCUGAGGACUAUAAUACCUUGGGAUGUGGACACAAUUUGUAAGUCUGUGAUCAAAACAGGGCGACUGCUAAUCAGUCACGAGGCUCCCUUGACAGGCGGCUUUGCAUCGGAAAUCAGCUCUACAGUUCAGAUAUACCCCCAUGAAAGAACCUCUGUUAAAUUUUCAGUAAAUUAAAACUUAAACGUCUCCAGAUGGGUCCAUGAAUGACUAAAAAAAAUCUUCUAGUGAAAAAUAACAAGAUCGUCAACAGAAAAAGUGACAAACAUAAAGUAUAUCUAGCCAUUAUAGAAAAUGUAAAAAAAAUUAUUUGUAUUCACAUUAGGCCUAUUUUAACACACAACACUGUGUAAAUGUCCAGAUUGACUUUUGUUAGACCAUAUUGUCAGAUUUAUUUUAGUAGAAGAUGAAGCACACACUUCAUAAUGGAGUAUAAAAUUUACCAAAGUUGUAGAUAAUCCAUUCAAAUGGAAUGUGUCUAUAUGUGUUUUGGACUACUUAACACUGCAAAUGCAACUUCAAAUAAUUAAAUUAAAAACAUAAAAAUUAUUCCCAAAAGUAAUAUCAUGGGCUACUUUACAUUUUAUUCAAUUUAAUCUAGCAAAAAAUUUUGAAUGCCAGAUACUGCAAAGAAUUCUACAAUCACAACUAAGGGGAUGGUCACUGACCUUGGAAGAGCUGAUAGUCUAGUGAGAAAUAAAACAAAUAUAUGAAUUAAUUAUAAUAUAAAAUAAAAUAAGAUGAACAAAAUUGGAAGACUAAGCUAUAAGGUCCACUAAGCAGUGGCUAUUUUUUUUCAUUUCCCCCCUAUGUAUACAAGUGUUUAUUUGUAUUAUUUUUACAAUUUGGGGAUUGUGCUGUGUGUUUUGAUUCCAGCUUAUUUUCAUUUUUCAUUGUAUCAUGGACAUUGUUUCAUAUUCUUAACUUGUUCAAAAGUCGUGUUUAAUGGCCAUAAGGUAUUCCAUCAUAUGAUAGUAAUUUAAAUAUUCCUCUAUUUUUGACCAUUUAGAUUGUUUACUCACUGCUACAAGCCUCAGAAGAAAUAAAAGAGCAAAAAUACCCCUAAACAUUUAUUAUUAAUGUAAAGUGUGUUCAAACAUGUUUUCUACUACAUACAUUAAGCAAAGUUACUAUCAGAUCUUAUAUUAUUGUAUAUAAUUUUGUAGAUAUAAUUAAACAGUACUACUCAGAUUAAAUGGGGAAAAAAAACCCAACACAGGUAGAUUUUCUUCUUCUUCUUCUUCUUUUUUUUUUUUUUUGAGACGGAGUCUCGCUCUGUCGCCCAGGCUGGAGUGCAGUGGCGUGAUCCCGGCUCACUGCAAGCUCCGCCUCCCAGGUUCACGCCAUUCUCCUGCCUCAGCCUCCCGAGUAGCUGGGACUACAGGCGCCCGCCACCACGCCCGGCUAAUUUUUUUGUAUUUUUAGUAGAGACGGAGUUUCACCGUGUCUCGAUCUCCUGAUCUCGUCAUCUGCCCGCCUUGGCCUCCCAAAGAGCUGGGUUACAGGUGUCAGCCACCGCACCCGGCCGUAGAUUUUCUUCUUAACUUGCCUUGCCAUUCACAUGUAUAUACCUACCACACAUAGAUUUUCAUAAUUGUACCCAAAUGCUAUAGUUUAUUGUGUACUUGCUAUUAUUUGCUAUAAAAUAUUUCUUUAUAAUAAACCUAUUGUGUUUUGGGGUGGUCUACUAUUAAAAGUAUAGUUUUUUUGUUUUUUGUUUUUUUUUUUAGACGGAGUCUCGCUUUUGCCAACCACGCUGGAGUGCAGUAGCAUGAUCUCGGCUCACUGCAACCUCCGCCUCCCAGGUUCAAGUGAUUCUCCUGCCUCAGCCUCCCGAAUAGCUGGGAUUACAGGCACUUGCCACCACACCUGGCUAAUUUUUGUAUUUUUAGUAGAGACAGGGGUUUCACCAUGUUGGCCAGGCUGGUCUUGGACUCCUGACCUCAGGUGAUCUGCCCACCUUGGCCUCCCAAAGUAUUGGGAUUACAGGAGUGAGCCACCAUGCCCAGCCAAAAGUAUAGAUUAUCAACAAUAAAUUUUAAUAUUGGGAGCUAUUCAAAGUGCAUUCUGUGUACUUUUUCUGUCUCAUACUUUCUACAGUCUCAUCCUUUCUAUAGUCUCAUCAUUAAUUUUAUAAAAAUAUUUAUCUUUGAAAUAUUUACUUGUGUAAUAAUGACUUUGUUAUUUUAACAAAAGAGUAAGUAUUCAUGUAUUUUGGCCUGUGGUUUUUUUUGUUUGUUUGUUUGUUUGUUUGUUUGUUUUACUGAAUAGCUUGUGGCUUGCCAUCUUUAUUUAACCAUCUGGUGAAAUGUUUCUCUUCCAUACUAAAAUGGCUUUAUUCUUUACCAUUUUACUUGUUAAAACUUUUAUUUUAGUAUCGGGGUACAUGUGUAGGUUUGUUAUAUAGGUUGUGUGUCACGGGGAUUUGGUGUACAGAUUAUUGGCCACACAGGUAAUAAGCAUAGUAACUGAUAGGUAGCUUUUCCAUCUUCACCCUCCUGCCAACCUCAGCCCUCAAGUAGGCCUCAGUGGUUUGCUGCCUUCUUUAUGUUCAUGUGUACUCAAUGUUUAACUCCCAUUUAUAAGUGAGAACAUGUAUUCAGUUUUCUGUUCCUGAAAUAAUUAGCUUAGGCUAAUGGCCUCCAGCUCCAUCCAUGUUGAUGCAAGGACAUGAUCUCAUUCCUUUUUAUGACUACAUGAUAUUGCAUGGUGUAUAUAUACAACAUUUUCUUUUUUUUUUUUUAAUUUCCAACUUUUAAGUUCAGGGUACAUGUGCAGAAUGUGCAGGUUUGUUACAUAGGUAAACAUCUGUCCUGGUGGUUUGCUACACAGAUCAUCCCAUCACCCAAGUAUUAAGCCCAGCAUCUAUUAGCUAUUCUUCUUGAUGCUCUUCCUCCUCCAACCCAAAGCCCUGCAUCAGGCUGGUGUGUGUCAUUGUCCCCAGUGUGUCCAUGUGUUCUCAUCAUUUAGCUCCCACUUAUAAGUGAGAACAUGUGGUAUUUAGUUUUCUGUUCCUGCAUUAGUUUGCUAAGGAUAAUCGCUUCCAGCUCCAUCCAUGUCCCUGCAAAGGACAUGAUCUUGUUCUGUUUUAUGACUGCAUAGUAUUCCAUGGUUUAUAUGUACCACAUUUUAUUUGUCCAGUCUAUCAUUGACAGGCAUUUAGGUUGAUUCCAUGUGUUUGCUAUUGUGAAUAGUACUGCAUUGAAUAUAUGUGUGCAUGUAUCUUUAUAACAGAACCAUUUAUAUUCCUUUGGGUAUGUAAUCAGUAAUGGGAUCGCUGGGUCAAAUGGUAUUUCUGUGUCUAGGUCUUUAAGGAAUUGCCACAUCAUCUUCCACAGUGGUUGAAUUUACACUCCCACCAACAAUGUAAAAGUGUUCCCUUUUCUCCACAACCUCACCAGCAUCUGUUGUUUUUUGAUGUUUUAGUAGUAGCCAUUCUGACUGGUGUCAGAUGGUAUUUCAUUGGGGUUUUGAUUUGCAUUUCUCUAAUGAUAACAGUAAUGUUGCACUUUUUUCAUGUUUGAUGGCCACAUGUAUGUCUUCUUUUGAGAUGUGUCCUUCUGUUCAUGUCCUUUGCCCACUUUUUAAUGAGGUUCUUUUUUUCUUGUAAAUUUGUUUAAGUUCCUUAUAAAUGCUGGAUAUUAGACUUUUUUCAGAUGGUGAUAUGGUUUGGCUGUGACCCCACCCAAUCUCACAUUGUGGGUGGGACCCAGUGAGAGGUAAUUGAAUCAUGGGGGCAGAUCUUUCCCGUGCUGUUCUCAUGAUAGUGAAUAAGUCUCAUGAGAUCUGAUGGUUUUAAAAAGGGGAGUUUCCCUACACAAGCUCUCUCUUUUUGUCUGCCAUCAUCUAUGUAAGAUGACUUGUUCCUCCUUGCCUUCCCCCAUGAUUGUGAGCCCUCUCCAACCACAUGGAACUGCAAGUCCAUUAAACCUCUUUGUUUUGUAAAUUGCCCAGUCUCGGGUAUGCCUUUAUGAGCAAUGGGAAAACGGACUAAUACAGAUGGAUAGAUUGCAAAAAUUUUCUCCCAUUCUGUAGGUUGCCUGUUUACUCUGUUGAUGGUUCCUUUUGCUGUGAAGAAGCUCUUAAUUAGAUUCAUUUGUCAAUUUUUGCUUUUGUUGCAAUUGCUUUUGGCAUCUUCGUCAAGAAAUCUUUGCCUGUGCUUAUGUCCUAUUGCCUAGGUUUUCUUCUAGGGUUUUUAUAGUUUUGGGUUUUACAUGUAACUCUUUAAUCCAUCUUGAGUUGAUUUUUGUAUAUUGUGUAAAGAAGGGGUCCAGCUUCAGUUUUCUGCAUACGAUUAGCCAGUUCUCCCAGCACCAUAUAAAACAGGGAAUUUUUUCUCCAUUGCUUGUUUUUGUCAGGUUCAUCAAAGAUCAAAUUGUUAUAGGUGUGUGGUUCUAUUUCUGGGUUCUCUAUUGUGUUUCAUUGUUCUGUGUGUCUGUUUUUCUACCAGUAGCAUGCUGUGUUGUUUACUGUAGCCUUGUAGUAUAGUUUGAAGUCGAGUAACAUUGAUGCCUCCAGCCUUGUUCUUUUUGUUUAGGAUUGUCUUGGCUAUUUGGGCUCUUUUCAGGUUUCAUAUGAAUUUCAAAAUAGUAUUUUCUAAUUCUGUGAAGAUUGUCAAUAGUAAGUUAAUGGGAAUAGCAUUGAAUCUAUAAACUGCUUUGGGCAGAAUGGCCAUUUUAAUGAUAUCAGUUCUUAUUAAUGAGUCUGGAAUGUUUUCCAUGUCUUUGUGUCAUCUCUGGAUUUCUUUGAGCAGUGGUUUGUAGUUCUCAUUGAAGAGGUCCUUCACUUCCCUUAUUAGCUGUAUUCCUAAGUGUUUUAUUCUUUUUAUGGCAAUUGUGAAUGGGAGUUCACAUUCAUAAUUUGGCUCUUGGCUUGCCUGUUGUUAGUGUAUAGGAAUGCUAGUAAUUUUUGGGCAUUGAUUCUGUAUCCUGAGACUUUGAUGAAGCUGCUUAUCAGCUUAAGAAUCUUUGGGGCCAAGAUGAUGGAUUUUCUAAAUAUAAGAUUAUGUCAUCUGCAAACAAAGAUAGUUUGACUUCCUCUCUCUUUAUUUGAAUAUGCUUUAUUUCUUUGUCUUGCCUGAUUGCCCUAGCCAGAACUUCCAGGACUAUGUUGAAUCAGAGUGAUGAGAGAGGGCAACCUUGUCUUGUGCUGGUUUUCAAGGGGAAGGCUUCCAGCUUUUGCCCAUUCAGUAUGAUAUUGGCUGUGGGUCUGUCAUACAUAUAUGGCUCUUAGUAGCUAGAGGUAUGUUCCUUCAGUACCUUGUUUAUUGAGCAUUUUUAACAUGAAGGGAUGUUGAAUUUUAUUGAAGGCUUUUUCUGAAUCUAUUGAGAUAAUCAUGUGGUUUUUGUUGUUAGUUCUGUUUUUGCCCUGAAUCACAUAUAUUGAUUUGCAUAUGUUGAACCAACCUUGCAUCCCACGGGUGAAGCCAGCUUGAUUAUGAUCGAUAAGCUUUGUGAUGUGCUGCUGGACUUGGUUUGCCAGCAUUUUAUUGAGGAUGUUUGCAUUGAUGUUCAUUAAGGAUAUUGGCCUAAAGUUUUUUGUUGUUGUAUCUCUUCCAGGUUUUGGUAUCAGGAUGAUGCUGGCCUCAUAGAAUGAGUUAGAGAGGAGUCCAUCCUUUUUGAUUUUUUGGAAUAGUUUCAGUAGGAAUGGUACCAAGCUCUUCUUUGUAGCACUGGUAGAAAUCAGCUGUGAAUCCAUCUGGUCCUGGGCUUUUUUUGUGGUUAGGCUAUUUAUUACUGCCUCAAUUUCAGAACUCGUUAUUAGUCUAUUCAGGGAUUCAGUUUCUUCCUGGUUCAGUCUUGGGAGGGUGUAUGUGUCCAGAAAUUUAUCCAUUUCUUCUGUAUUUUCUAGUUAACGUGCAUAGAAGUGUUCAUAGUAUUCUCUAAUGGUUGUUUGUAUUUCUGGCAUCAGUGGUAAUAUCCUGAUUAUUUAAUAUCCCAGUAUUUCUGAUUGUGUUUAUUUGAAUCUUCUCUCUUUUUUUCUUUAUUAGUGUAGCUAGUGGUUUUGUUUUGUUUUGUUUUUCUUUGAGAUGGAGUCUCGCUUUGUCACCCAGGCUGGAGUGCAGUGGCGCGAUCUCAGCUCACUGCAACCUCUGCCUCCUGGGUUCAAGCGAUUCUCCUGCCUCAGCCUCCCGAGUAGCUGGGAUUACAGGCAUCCGCCACCAUGCCUGGCUAAUUUUUGUAUUUUUAGUAGAGACGUGGUUUCACCUUGUUGGCCAGGCUGGUCUCAAACUCCUGACCUCAGGUGAUCUGCCCACCUCAGCCUCCCAAAGUGCUGGAAUUACAGGUGUGAGCCACCACACCUGGCCUGAGCCACCGCGCCUGACCUAUUUUAUUAAUUUUUUCAAAAAACCAGAUCCUAGAUUUGUUGAUGUUUUGAAGGGUUUUUUGUGUUGCUGCGUUUUUCAGUUCAUCUUUGAUCUUGGUUAUUUUUUGUCUUCUCCUAGCUUUGGGGUUUGUUUUCUCUUGGUUUUCUGGUUCUUUUGAUGUUCUAGUUCUUGUGAUGUUAGCUUGUUAACCUGAGAUCUUUCCUAGCUUUUUUACGUGGGCAUUUAGUGCUAUAAAUUUCCUCCUCAACACUGCUUUAGCUGCAUCCCAGAGAUUGUGGUGCUUUGUAUCUUUGUUCUCAUUAGUUUCAAAGAACUUCUUGAUUUCUGCCUUAAUUUCAUUAUUUACCCAAAAGUCAUUCAGAGCAGGUUGUUCAAUUUCCAUUUAGUUGUAUGGUUUUGAGUGAUUUUCUUAAUCUUGAGUUCUAAUUUGAUUGCACUGUUUAUUAUGAUUUCAGUACUUUUGCAUUUACUGAGGAGUGUUUUACUUCAGAUUAUGUGAUCCAUUUUAGAGUAUAUGCUGUGUGACAAUGAGAAGAAUGUAUAUGCUCUUCUAUUUGGGUAGAGAGUUCUGUAGAUACCUAUCAGGUCUGCUUGAGCUGUCACUCAGUCAGGAGAACUGGGAUCAGGGUCCCACUUAAAGGAGUAAUCUGGCUGCGUUUUGGUGGAGCAGCUGUACUUUACUGAGGACCCCUUUUGUCCCUGAUCCAUUUGGGCUGCCCAAGGUCCACAGGCUGGACCAGCUGAGAAACCCAAACAGCAAAGGUGGUGGCCUGCUCCACCCACCAUGCCCGCUGUCUUAGAGAGAAAUUAGAACUCUUGUCAGCUGUAGUACACAGAGGGAGGUGGCUGGAGACCCCAAGUGGGAGGACCCACCCUCGAGGGGGAUUUGUAACUCGGGGUCUCAUUUAAAGAAGCAGUCUGGCAAUGCCUCAACAAAACAGCUGUGCCAUGCUGUGGAACCACUUUUGCCCUGGUCAGCUUGGACUCUUCAAAGCCCGCAGGCUGGAACCGCUGAGUCGUCAAAACAACCAAGGUGGUGGCCUGCCCCUCCCGCAAGGCACUCUGUCCGAGGGAGAGACCAGACCUCUGUCCAUAGAAUAUGGGCUGGUAGGGGGAGCUCAGGCCUCUGGUGGGAGGUCCCACUUAGCGAGAAGGAAUAGAUCGGGGUCCUGCUUGAGGAAGCAGUCUGGCCACAUUCUGGCAAAGCAGCUGUGCUGUGCGGCGGGACUCGCUGCUCAUCCAGACCGUUUGUACUCUGCAAAGCCCACGGGCUGGAAUGGCUGAGUUGUUUAAACUGCAGAGAUGGCAGCCCACCUCUCCCCACUGGGGUUCCAUCCCCUCUCAGGCAGCCUCCACACUGUUUCCAGCUGCCUGGAAUUCCAAGCCACUGGGUCUUAUCUUGUGAGGAAAUGGGGCCUGUAGAACUGACACUGCUCAGCUCCCUAGAUUUAGCCGCCUUCCUAGGGGUAUGUAUGAACCUCCUGCCUUGCUGGGGAUCCCGGGGCCAGAGUAUGUAAAGCUCUGGGUCUCUGUGCUGCCUGAGCAACCGCUCUGUUGAGACUCCACAGAGUUCUGUGUGUUGGACCCAAGGCCCUGGUGGCAUGGGCUCAUGAGGGGAUCUCCAGAUCUGAGGGUUGCAAAGAUCCGUGGUUUCUUAGGGUUGUACAUUCGUUCACUGCUUCCCUUAACUGGGGGUGGGGGUUCCCUUGACUACAUGUCACUCCCAGUUGGGCCAUCACCUCACCAUACUUUUCUUCAUUCUCCCUGGGUUGAGUUGUUUUCCUGAUCAGUCCCAGUGCAAGUACCUGGAUAUUUCAGUAGAAGGUGCUGUAUUUACUCACCCCCCUUUUGUUGCUCUCUGUGAGUGCCACGCACUACAGUUGCUUCUGUUCCACCGUCUUGGCCCCCGAUCCCUUGUUUUUUUUUUUUAAGUUAUUUAUUUUUAUUUAUUUUUAGAGACAGGAUCUUGCCAUAUCUCCCAGGUUUGAAUGCAGUGGCACAAUCAUAGUUCACUGUAUCUUCGAACUCCUGGGCUCAAGGAAUCCUUCCACGUCGGCCUGCCAAAGUGCUGGGACUACAUGCAUGAGCCACCGCAACUGGCCUGUUUCCUUCGUCUAGAAAAUGAGGCUCUUAGUAGUUCACUGGCAUGGUGUAAGGAGUGAAUUAUGGAAAAUAUGUAAAGCACCUACCACAAUAUGUGGCAUAUAGUAAGCACAGAAUAAGUAACCAAUUCCUUCUCUUUUCUUCCUGUUUACACCGCAAUUUAGAGUAUUAACUGGCCUGUAAAAGAUUCUGUAAAGAAAAAUGCUGUAUCAGUUAGAGCCUUUUAAAAAGUGAAAAUAUCUUUCGGGGAUCUUCCUCCCAUCAGGCAAGUUGUUGGACUAGGGUCACUUCUAAGGUUUCAUUCCUAUGCUGUGAUUUUAGGAUUCCGAAACAGUGAAAAUAACUGGUAUGCUUCAUUAGGCAGUACAGUGUCAAGUUUAGGAUAAUUUACUUUGACAGAUCAUAAAACAGAUGUUAAAACAUUUAUAAACCUCAAUGAAUUAUUUUUUAAUUCACAGUCCAAUUAUCUUAAGAUUUUAAGCCAUGCUUGUUUUAGAUUUCCUUGAAUCAUAAUGAUUUUGUUUGCGUAUGAAAAGUAAUUCCAAUUCUGUAUCAUUAUGAGACAAAAUAUUCAGUGAAACUCAAACUGCUUUUUUUUUAUUUUUCAAAGCCUUUUUUUCCUUUUGCAUCGACUUUAUUUCAGUUCUUCAUAAGAAUAUAAAAUAUACUCCUUUUCAUCAGAACUUUUCUUCCACAGCCACUAAGUUCAUAUCAUAUGACUAUUUGGUGGGUAACAAUAUUAGCAAAUAUGUUUAUGAUAUCCAUUCUUUAUUUAACCUUACUCUUAAUAAAUGGAGAAAAUUAUGAAAUCAAGGUACUUCCCACAAGGAAUUCUUAAAGGGCUUUAUACCAAUAACUUUUGUCUUGUGACUUCUGUUUUCUUUGCCUAGAAGGAAUGGAAGAAAUGAGAGGAAACUGAUCUCAUUUGUUUUACUCUCUCAGUGGCUAGUUAUUAUUUCCCUGCAGCCUGAACAUUGGUUUUGUUACAGAGCUUUGUGGACUGCCUUCUUGUUUCAUGCAUAGACUAUGCCAACCUUGGAUCGCAGUGGAGGGCAGAAGCUAUUUAGAAGCACCCAACAGUGUGGCUUUUAUUCUGAUUGUUUUCAAAUGUGCUUAGUUGGCUCAAAUCAGGCUUCCCAGAACAGAAUCUUAGGGUGGGGUUUAGAAUUAGAGCAGCAUUUCUCCAGAAAGAUUUACGCUGUCAACCUUUUAUAAAUUAGGACUCUCACUGGGCUUGCUCUAAUUCUUUAAAACAUUUGUAUUCCAAUUGCUUUCAUCUUUGGUUGAGCUGUCUGGAUCAGAUGUGGCCGUUCUCUCUGAUUUUGCUUCUGAUACACACUUAGGGCCUGUGCAGUUUCUCUCCUUUACCCUUAAGGGGCAGACUUGACUAAAAUUCAAAGAUAUCUGUGUUUUCUAUUGCUGCCAAAAUACCCAAAUACCGUUCCAAAAUACCCAAAACUUAAAGGGUACACCCCCAACUUAAAGCAACACAGAUUUAAUGUCUUACAGUUCUGUAGGUUUAGAGUCCAACACACAUAUCAAUGGUCUAAAAUCAAGGUGUCAACAGAGCCGCAUUCCUUUCUGGAGAAUUCUCUAGGGGACUAUCUGUUUCCUAGCCCCAUCUAACUUCUUGCGGCCUCUCACAUUUUUUGGUUCAUGGCUCUUCUUCUGUCUUCAAAGCCACAGAAAUUGCAUCUCGCGCAUCUCGCUGACCCUUCUUCUAUAGUCACAGCAUCUGCUCAAUGACCACAGCUAGGGGAAGUUCACCAAUUUUAAAGGCAUGUGAUUAGGUUGGGCCCAUCUGGGUAAUCCAGGCUACUAUUCCCAUCUCAAGGUUUUUAAUUACACCUGCAAAGUCCCUUUUGCCAUGUAAGGUAACAUAUUCGUAGUUCGAAGGAUUAGGACAUGGACAUUUUGGGGACAAUUAUUCUGCAUAUCACAAUCCCUUUCUCUUUUCCUUAGUAGACCACACUAGUCUGGUGACUUGAAGGAACCUAGCCAUUUCUCUUCUACCUCACCACAGUGGGCCCAGGAUAUAGUCAUUUUAAAAACAUAAAACCCAGUGUAUCAGGCUCCAGGCCAGGGCUUCUCAGCUGACUGUUUCUAUUGGUGUAACAGACUGGAUUUUGGCUGUCUCUCCCUCUACUUUCCUCCAGCAGUCUUUGGUCUUGUUUUGAGAUGUUUUCCCUCCUGUGGUCCUCAGUCUGCCAGUGUUCUUCCUAUAACUUUAUCUCUGUGUGUCAGGAUAUACACUGUACUCUAUAGAAAUGGCAGUGGAACCCCAACAAUUGUGGGUGUUUGGGUAAUAAUCCACAACCUUAUCAUUCCCAACACCCUUCCCAUUGUAGCUUUCCUCUAUAAAGAGAAGUUUGGAGCUCCUAAAACCAGAUCUGAAAUUUAUUUAUUCAAUUAAUCAUUCAAAUGUGCAAGAUGUGGGGAGAAUUGGAUAUAGAGAUAUGGCUCCUGCCCUCAAGAAAUUAAUAGUCAAACAGGGAGAAGGACAUGAAAUACAAGCAUUGCUGUAUGUGGGAUGGAUGUCUGUAUAUACAGUUGGUCCUCUGUAUGUAUCCCUGUGUUCUUCAUCUGUGGGUUCAACCAACCACAGAUCAAAAAAAUUGGGGGCUAGGCGUGGUGGCUCAUGUCUGUAAUCCUAGCACUUUGGGAGGCCAAGGCAAGUGGAUCACCUGAGGUCAGGAGUUCGAGACCAGUCUGACCAAUACGGUGAAACCCCAUCUACUAAAAAUAUAAAAAUUAGCCGGGCAUGGCAGCAUGCACCUGUAGUCCCAGCUACUCAGGAGGCUGAGGCAGGAGAAUUGCUUGAACCCGGGAGGUGGAGGUUGCAGUGAGCCAAGAUUGUGCCACUGCACUCCAGCCUGGGUGACAGAGUGAGACUCUCUCUCUUAAAAAAAAAAAAAAAAAAGAAAAGAAAUUAGAAAAAAAAAUUGUACUGAACAUGUACAGACUUUUUUUUUAUUGUCAUUGUUUCCUAGGCAACACAGUGUAACAAUCAUUUACAUCAUAUUAUGUAUUGUAAAUAAUCUAGAGAUGACUUAAAGUAUAUGGGAGGAUAUACAUAGAUUAUAUGCAAAUAUUACACUAUUUUAUAAAAGGGACUUGAGCAUCUUCAGAUUUUGGUAUCUAUGGAAGGUUCUCAAGCCAAUCCUUUAUGGAUACCAAGGGUUGACAUAUGUGUAUAUUUAUAUAUGUGUGUUAGUUAUCUGUUAUAAUGGGAGCACAGGAAAGAUAAGCCCUUAAAUUUCCCUCAGGGAUUCAGGGAAAGUUGUCCAGAGGCAGCUAGGGUUGAGCAGCAGAUGUCAUGACACUACUAACCAGAUAAGUCUUCUCCUUUCACUCAGGCCUUAUGGAAUAAGCUAUGCUUGUGGAAUUUUUUAUGUGGAAAAGAAUUACAUGAAACAAUCUGCAUUGCUCUUCUCACUGUUUUUAGAGGGAAUCAGUAGGAAUCAGAAUACUGGCUGACUCUUUAGGUAUGUGGGCUUAUAUGAAUUUUUUAGCUCUUUAAUCCUUAGUUUUUCCAUUAGUAGUACCCAACUUGCUGAAUUGUGAGGUUUGAAUGAAUUAUUAAAGUUAAGCUUUUAGAAUGGGACCUACUACCCAGAAAAUAUUUAACAAUAUUAUUGUAAUGUAUCACUGUCACCAUUUAUUACUACAAUCUCUCUUGAAUUACUCAUCACUUUUCUGACAUCAUCAUAUGAAACAAGUUUUUUAAUUCAUGCCAGCUUCUCCCUCUUACUUACGGUUUAGGAGUUGCCUCUAAUGCCUAAGGAAACGUGUAGCCCUCUGGUUGUACUGCAAAAGUGGUUGCAUUUUGAAGGCAGGUGUAUACAACUUCCAGAGUAAGAAUAUGUGUAUUCAGGUGUAGGCGUUGUCAGUUUCCAAUAAGAUAAUUUAUAAUGCUUAAUUUAUAUUAGGAAGAUCUCACAUUGUUCUCUUCUGUAAAUUAUGCAUGUAUUUGUAAAUCUAAAAGGAACUUUGAUUUUUCUCUCUGAUUAAGGUGUAUAAUUAUAAUCUUAAAUAAAAGUGAAGUUCAAAGUAGCUUCAUUUAAAAUAUUAAUAGACAAAACAUAAGAUCAGUUCUUUUAGGGAUUGGUUUGUCAGCCACAUGUUAGAUCUGCUUAGAAAUCUUCAGUGAAAUAGGAAACAUUGUAUAAAUGUUACCUAAUGUAAAUACUGCUAAAUUUAAGAUAUACUAAAAUUUGAGUAUUUUCCCUUUAGUCUCAAAUAAGCAAAAGGAAAUCUGAGUUAUAUGAAAAUGAAAGCAUGUAUUCAGCUUUUAUAAAACCAUUAUAAAUAAGUUAUUUUUCCUACCAAGUUAAAUAGGAUAUGUUUACAUGUUUUAAAUUUUAGUUUUAUUAGUUACAGUAUCAUAUUGUGAAUAGUAGCAAAUAUGUCCUUAUAUAGUUCUGGGUUCUUGCUUUAUAAUGUACAUAGACAAAUAUCUUUUUAAAAAAAUUUUUGUGUUCCACAGACGCAACAGGUUUUGAUAAUUUCUUAUUUCACCUGUUGGUUACAGUCACAAUAAUAUGUUCUUUCUUCUACCUUAUGAUUGACCAUUUCUGACAUAAAAGUUAAGAAUUUGUAUCAUCUAAACAGCCUUUUAUGUCCUUUCUCUUUUUUCAUACAUCUUGAUAAUUGUAGUGUUUUUCAUGUUUGCUUCUAUUUUCUAUCUUUCCGAGUUUGCAAAACAUUAUUAAAACUUCAUUUCUAGUUCUUCACUAAUAGGACCCAAAUCUAAGUCUCUCAACUUCAGGCUCUACUUAAGUAUCCAGAGUUCACAAUUCAGCGACCGUUUCCAGGGUGGAGGCCUGUAGAAGAAUCAGUCCUAUUUUUACAAAAACAGAGAAAUUUGUGCUCCUAAUAUUUGCAUAGUCAUAAAAUUGCAAAAGUUAUAUUGGUUUUACAAUUUUAAAUUGAUAGGCAAUUAUGAUUUUUGCAAAUGACAUUCUAAUAAAAAUUAUCAACAUUUGGUUAUGGUAGCGAUGGUGAAGAAACACAGUGAAAGCAAAUAUUUUCUUAUGUCACUUAUACAUGUACAACAAUGGCCAUAUUUCUGAAAUGUAAAUGAAAGUAUAAUGCCUUCUUCGAUUUUUAUUUUGACCACUGAGUAAAUUAAACCUUCAAUAAUCUCAUAAAAAUGAGAUAUUUUCUUGCUAUACCUCUGAUAUCCCCUGUCCCCUGAAAAAAUAUGAAAUUAGUACAGAGCCAGUAAAAAAUACCAAGAACACCCAGGAUAGAUUCUAUCCUAACCUAAACAAGCUUAUAUUAUGAAAGUGGUGUUAUUUUUUAACAGAUCAUAAAUUAGACAAUAUAGUUCAUCUAGGGCCGAUAACUUCUCCCCAUGCAGCUGUUGUCACUCUUGGGAGGUGCUUCCUAGAAUGUGUGCUGAGAAGGAUGCUAUAAUUAGUGAUGUCUGCCUUGGGUACAGAAUAUCAGUAGUGGUUAGGAGCAGUACACAUUUUCCAUCCUUAAGUAUCUGGAUGGGAAGAGAUCUAGAGAACAGAAUAUCAUAUGUCUCCUGACUCAUAACUUGGGAUCUUUCCUCAAUUCUACUGAAUAACCUGUAGUGGAAAACCAUGUUUCUAUAGUCCUAUCCCUCGUCCAGGUGGAUUAUCUGAACAGGACUCCUGUGGAAUGGUUGUGGUAAUGUAAUUCAUGUGGACAUUGACAAGUUGCCAUCAUGUGGUCAUGAGGAUGGUGUUGGAUUCCUUAUGUGUGAGGCUGAUAAGGGCCCUAUGUUCAAUUCUUAGUGGUCCUUUUAAACCUACACCUGUUUAUAUUUUUUAUCAACAUGCCCAUAACUUAUUUUUCGUGAAUCCACUGAAACUUCCAGAGACUUGAACUUUGCCUAAAGUUUAAAACAGGAAUUUUUUAAAUCCCUUAAAUGAAAAAUAGUUUUAAGUGUAUCCCAACUAAUAUGAAACAGGAAACUAAUGUCUAAUAUCCUUGGGAACUAUAAAAUAUUCAAUAGUAAUCAAAACAUAAAAUGAUUCUCUUCUGUCUUUCCGUUAUUCUCUACUUCCAAUUACAUUUUGUAAAAUGUAAACAAUUGCACCUGCAAUUGAUGGAAAAAUACCAUCAUGAAAUCAAAUGUGUUUUCUGACUUCAUAUAUGUAUUGUAGUAUUUAAUAUUAAGUAAGCUCAGAAGAUACUUACAUGGAAUCUACUGCCUUUUCUGAGCACAAGAGAAGCAAUGAUUAAUAGAAUGUGGUACUUGCUCCAAGGAGCAUUCAUUUAAGAGGAGGGAUGCUCCUAUUUGGGUCUUCACUGUAUAAAGCAUUUAUAUGUAUAUUACUUAACAACUAAAAGGUAUGUACUUAUGCAGAAUACUGCCAUCAUUGCUCUUUUCUUUACUGUAAUGGUACCAUUCAUCAGGUCCAUGGAAGCCAGCUUCUCACACAUUCUCUCUUAGACAUAGGCGUUUUCUUUCUUUCUUUUCUUUUUUUUUUUUUUUUUGGUGACGGAGUCGCACUUUGUUGCCCAGGCUGGAGUGCAAUGGCACAAUCUCGGCUCACUGCAACCUCUACCUCCCAGGUUCAAGUGAUUCUCCUGCCUCAGCCUCCCGAGUAGCUGGGAUUACAGGCGCGCACCACUACGCCUGGCUAAUUUUUGUAUUUUUAGUAGAGACAGGGUUUCACCAUGUUGGUCAGGCUGGUCUCGAACUCCUGACCUCGUGAUCCACCCGCCUCGGCCUCCCAAAGUGCUGGGAUUACAGGCAUGAGCCCCCACACCUGGCAGACGUGUGUUUUCUAAAGUGGAUUUAUUAGAAAUUGGGAUCCCCUUAACCAUCUUUACUUAGAGGAGACUUUGGCUUAGUGACCUACAGUUGUGUGUAAAUGAAAAGCAAAAUUAAUGGGAAGUAUACUCACAAAAGAAGGACUUUAAAGUUGCAAAAAUAGCAUGCAUCAAGAAUAGUAUAAAAUUUUAAUUCCUCCAUCGUCACCAAUAAACAUUUAUGGAGAAUCCCCAGAGUGACUGACUCUGGAUUUUACAUCUUAUGUUAAACUAACUCUUGCAUUCUGUUCUUGCUGUUUUAUAAUUACCCCAAAUGUUCUCUGUUACUUCUCCUAAUGAUUCUUCUUUUUUUUUCUUUUUUCUUUUUUUUUUUUUUUUUGCAUACAGCAGAGAAUGCCUGUGGGUUUAAAAAUUUUUUAACUAAUCUUGAUGAAUCAAUUAUAAUUUAUAAAAGUGGAGCAUAACAGUUAAGAGCUCAUGCUAUGGAAUUGGACAGAGCUGAUUUCAGAUACUGUUCUGCCACAUGCAAAGUGCAUAACUGGACUAGUCACUUACCUUUCUGAACCUCAGUUUCCUCAUCUCUGAAGGGGAUGAUGAAGGUUCAGCCCUCUCAUAGGGCUCAUGACAAUUAAUGAGAUAAUGUCACAUGCUUAAUACCAGCAUCUUGUAUGCUCCAUAGGUGUUAGCUGUCUGUUUGUAAUAAUAUUUUUGUGUUUGGUUACACAAACCCACUUUCUUCAUUUGUUUUCUGCUAUUAAUGCCUUUUGAAGUAUUGUGUUGUUUGUGAACACAUAGUACAAAUUGACUUUUGUUUUUUUAAUUAUCAAUUUUGUUUCUGUAACUGCACAGAAAAGUGAUAAAUUGUGAGCUUAUAUUUUCUUUUAAUACAUAGAUAUCGCCUCCCAACAUACAUGAAUUUUAAGACACUAAAAACCCCUUAAAGAUCUUUUCUUAAUCAGUGUUUAGUAAAUGGGCUUACAUUCUAGCGUAUAGACCAAUUCAAACUGUUCUACAGUAGAGAGGAAUUUGUAUGUUGGCCAGUUUUUCAUACAGUGAUUUCUAACUCUUUCCCCUUCAGUAUUUCCCUAACAUACACUUUCUCAUCCAGUAUUUCUUUUAGAAUUCUCACACUUUUGCCCUCAUAACUCACUUUCAUAUUCCUAGAGCUCUUUUCUUCACACUGAUUGUGCUGCUCCUUUUCAAUUUUUCCAACCUUAUGGAAUUAUUAGUGAGAAAAAGCAAAAUUAUUAUUAUUUGAGACGGAAUCUCGCUCUGUUGCCCAGGCUGGCGUGCAGUGGCGCCAUCUUGGCUCACUGCAAGCUCCGCCCCCCGGGUUCACGCCAUUCUCCUGUCUCAGCCUCCGGAGUAGCUGGGACUACAGGCGCCCGCCACUACGGCCGGCUAAUUUUUUGUAUUUUUAGUAGAGACGGGGUUUCACCGUGUUAGCCAGGGUGGUCUCGAUCUCCUGACCUCGUGAUCCACCUGCCUCGGCCUCCCAAAGUGCUGGGAUUACAGGCGUGAGCCACCGUGCCCGGCCCAAAAUUAUUUUUUAUAUAUGGUGACUUUCCCCCACCCUUUCAUCUUACAGUAGAGGCAGCUCAGAAAAAAAUCACUGAAUUAAGUCAUUCAGAGGUCGUUUAUAAUAGCUAUUCAGCAGUGAGCUGGUUCUCAGUCCUGGUUAUCCAUUACAAUUUCCCAGCAUUUAAAAUUCUGAUACCGUGACCAUACCCAAGAAUAAUUAAAUAAGACUUUCUGUAGGUGGGACCUAGGCAUCUGUUUUUAAAGCCCUUCAGGUGAUCUUAAUGGGCAGCUAAGUAUGAGAGCUACUAUAGGACAGUGUUGUAUGGCCUGAUUAGGUAGGAAUGAGAGGGAGAGGAAGAAAUCAGGACAGGAGAUGUAGACUUAUUUUGAUAAGUUUUGGUAGUGAAAGGCAGAAAAGAGAUGGGACUGUAACUUAAGGAAUUAGCAGGAAACACAACAUACCUGAGAAAGAACAUUCUAGCAUAUAUAUAUAUAUUAGCAUAUAUAGUAGUGAGUCUCAGCUACUCCCCUAGGGCAGUGUAUCAGCAAUUUAGGAACCAGGGAUGAACAUGCAUUUGGCAAAACUUCCUAAUUUUGAUACACCUUUCCCUUUCUCACUACCCUCCCUUCUCUCUUCUCUCCCCAGCCCCUGUCUACAAUACUGCUAUCCUGCUCCCUCUGCUCCUCGUCCUUUUCUUUCUUAAACUGGGUGACAGAGCAUCUCAAAGUUGACUUCCCUCAUGGUGGCCAUAUGGCUCCAGCAGUUCUCAGCAAGAGUUCUGAAUUCACCCUGAUUAGACCAUUAAGGUCGUAUUUCAACUAGUAACUGAGGCUGGGGGAAUGGAAUAUGCUCAUUUGUGAAGUCAAUCAAGAAAGUACAUAGGAAGAUGGGAAAGGAUGCUGGUAGACAGCCAGUACUACCCACUAUAUAUGUAAAAGUCACAGUGAUUCAAUGCAAUCAGUUAUUUUACAUGUGCAAAUUAUGAGUGGUCUUGUAUGGGGACGGUUUUGAAUAACAUAUAGAAAGUACUAUAUAGUACUGAUAUUUUUCUGAGCAUCAAAUAUUUAGAGAAAAAAAUCUGUGGUGUUUUAGAAUAUAAUAUAAUAAACAUCAAAUAAUUUACUAGAUCAAACAUGGUUUAUUAACUUAAACACUGUAGCAUAUAGCAGUCUGUAGCACAUCUUACUGACUGAUCCUUUUUUGAAAAAAUCAUUACUUCACAUUGUUGAUGUUGUGGCAGAAUCUAGGACUUCUAUAAUUACAUUUCUGGAGAUUAUCAGGCAAAUGUGUGGCUUUUACCUUUUCUGGUUACUAUUUUAUAGAAAAAUGUAAUUGCUAGGUAUGUCAUUUAAGACCCUGCAAUCUAUUUGUCUGAAAAAUGGAACAAAUGCUAGUAAGAAUUUUAAAUGACUCUCAAAGCCUCCUGCAAAAUGACAUUAGCAGUUGAAAUAAAAUAGUUAACAGUCUAAAAACUGUUUAAGAUAAAGCCCAUAACUAUUAAUUUUAGGACUGUUUUGUAUACAAUGUAAAUGACACAUGUUUGAGUUAAUCCAUUUGAUGGUGGUGAUCACAUUCUUAAGAAAUGAUUUGGUAUCUCAAAGCAGUUUCUUAACUAGACAAUGAGCAGAAAACCUGUUGCUAGUUUUGGAAGUUUAAAUUGUCAAACUUCAAUUACUUCUGUUUAAUUUGGGAUUAAAGUUUGGGAUUAAAAACACAUGAGCAAAAAUCUCAUAACCCCAGUUCAGUCAUGAGAGAAACACCAGACAAAUUUCAGUUGAGGGAUAUUCUACAGAAUAUAUGUCCAGUACUCCUCAAAACUGUCCAAGUCAUCAAAAAACAACAAAAGUCUGAGAAACUGUCGCAGCCAAGGGAUACUAAGGAAACAAGAGGACUGAAUGUAAUUUGGAUUCUGGAUGGGAUCCCAGAGUGGAAAAAGGACAUUAGAGCAAAACCGAGGAAAUCUCAAUACAGGUUGGGCUUUAGUUAAUGUGUCAAUACUGGUUCAUUAAUUGUGACAAAUACACUAUAUUAGUGUAGGAUGUUAAUAAUAUUAACAAUGGUGGAAACCGGUUGUGGGAUAUAUGGGAAAACUGUGUACUGUUUUCAUAGUUUUUAUCUAAAUUUUAAAAUACCUCAAAAUAAAACGUUAUUUUUAAAGAUGUGGGGAUACAUUUUUCAGGAAAGAGUCUCCGCCAUAAGCUUACUAUAGCAGAGCCUGAAUGCUACUGUUUGAUGAAUGAAAGAAGUCCGGUAUUCUUGGAGAUCUUCUCUGUAAUCCUCCAGGCUGAGGCAUCACUUAGAUUUGGCAUUUGAGACCUUUAUUGUUGACCUAUGAAAUUCUGUUUUAUGUCUGUCUCUCACUUUGUUUCACCAUAGUAUAGUAUAGGUUAUAGGAGCAAGAAAACUGAUUUUUCUUUCAAGAUCCACUGUAUGCCAAUCAUGUACUGGAUUUCACUAAAAUUAACACAUCCAAUUUUUAGAAACUUUGUAGGAUAGAGGACUACCCUUUCUACAAAAGAGGAAAACAGACUAAGAAGAGUAAGUUACUUGGCCAGGCACAGUGGCUCACACCUGUAAUCCCAGCACUUUGGGAGGCCGAGGUAGGUAGAUCACUUGAGGUCAGUAGUUCGAGACCAGCCUGGGCAAUAUGGUGAAACUCCAUCUCUACUAAAAAUACAAAAGUUAGCAGGGCAUUGUGGCUUGUGUCUGUAAUCCCAGAGAAUUGCUUGAACCCAGGAGGCAGAAGUUGCUGUGAGCUGAGAUCGCACCACUGGACUCCAGCUUGGGCAACAGAGCGAGACUCAGUCUCAAAAGAAAAGAAAAAAAAAGAGUAAGUAACUUGCCCAGAGUCACACAGAUGUUUACUGACAGACUACAUGAGAGCCUUGUUUAUUACUUGACUCCAAUUUCCAGCCUUUCUACCUUCUCAUAUAUAUGCCUUCUUUGUUAUCGUAAGAUUCAGAUUAGCAAGGUACUCUUUUUAACCUGUGCCUAUGUUUUAAAAAAAAAUUGUUUAAGUUUGACAUAAGUAUAAGCCAGCAGGAAGUUGCAAAAACAGUACAGAUGCUCCCCAACUUAUGAUGGGGUUACCUUCCAGUAGACUCAUUAUUGAAAGUAUCGUAGGUCAAAAAUACAUUUAAUACACCUAACCUGUAACUUAGCCUUGUAUGCUUUAAGUGUGGUCAUUAGCCUACAGUUGGGCAAAAUCAUCUAACACAAAGCCUAUUUUAUAAUGAAGUGUUGAAUAUUUCAUGUAAUUUAUUGAAUACUGGAAGUGAAAAACAGAAUGGUUGUAUGAGUAAAGUACGGUUUCUACUGAAUACAUUUUGCUUUUGCACCAUUGUAAAAUCAAAAAAUUUUUAAGUUGAACAUUUCUUAAUUUGGGGACUGUAUUAGUUCAUUCUCACAAUGUUAUAACAACAUACCUGAGACUGGGUAAUUUAUAAAGGAAAGAGGUUUAAUUGACUCACAAUCCCACAAGGCUGGGAAGGUCUCAGGAAACUUGCAGUCUUUUGCAUUUCACCAUGAAAGAGUUCGUCCAACUUUUUAGGUUUUUAUUACAAAAUAAAUAGUGUUUUCUCUGCCCUCUCUGUACCUCGUAUUUGAGGAAUUCUCAUACUUCUCUUUCAAGAUGUCUUUCCCCACCCAUUUUGUUUAUGGUGGUAAUAUUAUACCAAUAUGGCCAGCUUUUAUGUACUUUGUGAUCUCGCUACUAUGAAGUUAGCCCCCUUCAGCAUUUAUUCAGAAUAAUGCCUCUUAAAAAAGUGUUUAAUGAUUUCAUAAGGUCCUUGGUGUUUCUUAAUGUCUUCCUUUCUCUUUUUUCCCUCCCCUUUUCCCCUCCCCUUUUCUCCCCUCCCUUCUCCCCUCCCCUCCCUCCCUUCCUUCCUUCCUUUCAUUUUUUCUCUGUGACCAUCUGUAUGUUCUUUUCUUUUUGUCUGCCUUUUAGUAUUAAAAUGGUCACCUGACGACCAUCUGAGUUGAGCUUUGUCAAGAACCAAGGGCUGAAGUUCUUUUUGUUCAGACUAUGUUUCUGUUACCAGUAUUGAGGGACUAAGGACUUUCAAGCCCUUCUCAUUCUCCCAGCCUGAGAGAUAUUAAGAUAAGGGAAAACUAGAUUUUGCAGGUAAACUUUGAUUUGUUGAAUGCCUGCUUUGUGCCAGACAUUGCAUGCUACGAUAUAUUCUAUUAAAAGGAUUCAGGAAGGGCAUUUACUCUUUUAGCUACUGGAGUUUGAUUUUCUUUAUUAUCAUGCUGAUCAGUGUACACUGGCAGUGUGGCUGAUUGAGUGGAAAAGGGAGAGCUACACUGUCUUGUCACUCACCUAGUUGAUAACAGAUUCAGGACAAGGACUCUCGUCUCCUUUCUAAUACAAUAUUAGCCCUAAACCCAAAGAAGUUGAGAUGUUUUGUCAUUCUUUAGUUUUUCCCAAAGGGAACAUUUUUCACAACAUAAAAAGUUAGCUGAUUGGAAUUAACUUAUACUUUAUAAGAGAUCAGUGCAUAUCUAGAGGCGACAUAGUAGAAUUUUCAAACAAUCAGAAAUCUCAUAAAUCGGAAUCUAAGGGAAAACAAAUAUACCCUCCUGAACGUUGUAUAAUUGGGUAUACAGAAAACUUUCUAAUUUUAUUUUGCCUUCAUUUUUAGACUAACUUGCAAUUACCCCAAGUUGCUAGGUAGCAAAAUUAUUAUGGUACUAGCUCAGAAUUUGCUGUAUUUUAAUCAGCCUUAGUGACUGAAAACACAGAGAGAAUGUCAAUGAGGGAGAAAGGUUUUCCUUUACUGCCCCUAGAUAAAGCAGAUGAAAAUCUGUUUCUCUCCACGGUAGAUUCCUACUCCUUGCCAAAGAUACAAUAGACAACAUUUAUAAAAAUACAAUCUUUGUGCAUGUUGCUAGGUUGCUCAAUUUUGAGCCUUUUUCUUUACAAUACAUAAUCAUUUAAAAAAUACUGAAAGAGGUAAGAAAUAGGGAGUGGAAACCAGUAGUGUGAGUAAAUGGGAAAUUGAUAUCUUUAAGGCACUAGAUAUGGUAAUAAAUAUAUUAGAUUACUAGAAGAGAAAAAAUACUUGAAUAGUAGCCAAGAAAGGAUUCCAAUUACUUACAAACUACAGUGACUAACUUCUUUCAAUUCUAAAAUCCCCUAUUUUAAUUUUUCUAAGUUUCUGAGAAAUGGGCAUUUUAGUAUUACUCCUUAAAAACUUUUUUACUGAAUAAAAUAAUUUUCAUGAAAUUACAAAAACAUAGGAUCUGCUCAUAUUGAUAGUGUGUUUGACUUACCACUCACUGUAUUGUGUCUCACUUAGAUUACCAGCAAAAAUAUUACUCACAUCUAAUGAUAUUUCUGGGUAUCCUAUAAAUGAACCCUGAGAGGUUUCCUGGAGAGUCUUGUAAUGCUUCCUAGCUACCCCUGUAUAUAUUCUAUAAAAUAUAGCCAUGUAAAGUAUGAAGACAAUCUGUUACUGUCUUCCUGGCAGGGCUGGUCAACUGGCCAUCAGACACUGUGGUUGCAUCUGGUUGUCCCCUGCUUCCUACUGCUCCAUUGUCCCACUUUGGGUGUCUCCCCCUCCUCCCUGUGCUGGUGCUGCCCUUUCAUAGGCCUUCUCUCAAUAACUGGAUCUCACCAGGCUCCUUUCUGCAUUCCUAGCUUUGUACUUGCUGUGUGACCUGGCAGGAGUGCUUCUCCUGGGUUCUUUGCAGAUCUGGUUUCUCCUUCUCAAAUGACACCACCUUAGAAAGCCCUUUCCUGAGCAUACUGUGCAACUCAGAGCUCCCUGUUAGUCUCUAUCACAGACCCCUUACUUACUUCCUUUUUAGCACUCCUCAAACACCUUCCCCCAACUAAAACAUAAAACUCUAUGAGGAUAGGGACAUUGUGGACACUCACAUAUUAAUAAGUGAUUGAAACAUGAAUGCAUUUUUAAAAAGAUCAGUACCAACAUCCUAAAGGCUCGUGGAGAAGGGCAUUUGAGCUGACUUUGAAAAGUAGAAUGUGAAGAUAGCAGGGUGUAGGAAAACAAGAGUUUUAGAAGAGAGAGGCUUGUGUCAAGGUGAUCUUAUAAAAAAAAAAAAGCUUUGGUAUGAAGGCAGGCAUGUGCAUGUCUUUACUGGGCUUUGUGGAGAAAAUAGAGAUAAAGAAUAAACUUUGGGGAACCAGGAAAACCUUUUAUCUAGGAAAGGGACAUGAUCAAAAUGGCACCAGUGUGGCAUCUAGUGGAUGAGUUGAAGGUUCAGGAAUUGCUAAGAAGUAAAAGCAUCCACACCCUACUUCCUGUCUUGCUGACAUAUAUAUAUAUUUGGCCUCAUCAGUAGCAAAGCUCAUUAAUACUCCAGGAUGAUACAGAAUAGAAAUACAAACUGGAAUUGUUUGUUUAAUCUAUAUUUAUGCAUUCACAAAUAUUUACUGAUCCCUGCUCCAUGUCAGUCAUUGUACCUCUGAUCCAUUUGGGCUUGUAAAUCUGUGUAUGUGAUACUUGGAGAUGUUUUUGCAUACCUAAAAUGAGACACCACUUAAGAGAUUUAGCUGUUGAUACUCGAACCAGUGAAGACAAAGCUGGCAAAUACCUCCCUAAAUAGGAAGGAUAUGUAUUUAAUUUGGAAAAUGUCAAUUUAUUUGUUACCCUACACAGUAAGAAUUAGAUAUCUAGAAACAACUACAGGUAUGAAAUAUAACUGUUGAAAUGUGUGCUUCUUUUAAGAAACUCCAAGAGCUACGUGGAAGCAUGUGUUGUUUUCUUGUCAGUUUUCCUUCUCAUAUGACAUUUGCUCCUAAAAUACCCAAUUUUUUUUCUGCCCAGACCUACACACCCAACCCACUUUAGCUGUACCAUCCUUAGAUUACUAUGUCACAAAUUUUACCUUGUUUUGAAACUGAAGUACAGUGGCUGAUUUUGCUAUUUUUGCAUUUAUUUGCAAAGCUGAAUUCUAGUAAUUACCAGCAAAGAUAAUCGUUUUGCACAAAAAGAGGUAUAUUUCUAUCUUGAAACUAGGUUAUAUUGUUAAUGCCACAGAAAAGGAAAUGGCUUUUUCAGAAUAUUAGCGUUUGUAGCUCUUGCUUAUUGAUAGGGAAAAGUUAGUUGCCAUAGUGAUCUAACAGCCUCUGGAGGGAAUGCAGUCAUGGCCUUAAGCAUCCGGCAACCCACCCAGUUGAGAGAGCCCCUCUGAAAAGGAUUUCCUUCCAUGGAAAUUGAGUUUCUAAAAUAAAAAGAGUUUAUUUUAGCUUAGAUUUGCUUAUAGGUUUGUUUUGCACUUUUACCUACUGGAAUUAAAGGAAAAACAUUUAUAAUAAAGACAGCAUAUAUUUCUUCAGGGAUGACAUUAAAUAAUAGAUUUUUGUGUUAACCAUUCCAUAAAUGUGCUCUCAGACACACAAAAUGACCUUUAUACUUUUAUUCUUGUGAGCUAUGGAGCUUAAAAGCAAACCACUUCAACCAGAUGUUGAUCCAAUAAAUUUAUCAAUAUUUGGGGUUUUUAGAGUUUCAGUAUAUAUUCUUAGGUAGAGGGAACUUUCAUGGCCCAUCAAAAUCUGCUCAAGCUGUGCUGGGUGAAACAGCACUCAUCUAUAAUACUCAUGUAACAUGAGCCAAUCUGCAGUCGGUUGUUCUGAAUUCUACAUCACUCACAGCGCAGGUUGAUGUGUGAACACUGUAUUUACAGGACCAAAACUGCACAUUUGCUCUGCAGCUGUGUUUAACAGUUAUCAGUUUGGCACACAGCAUGACUGCUUUGGAGGGAGAAUAGACACUUCUCAUCCCUUUUGGCAUUUAUGAAGUAACCAAAGUACCUACUGCUGAAGUGAUUCACUUGAGCUUAAUUAGAUUUGCUACAUAAUUAGCAUUUGAAGAAACCUAAAGAAAAUCCUUGGGGGUUGGUUAUUUGUUAUGUCAAUUGUAAGCAUGCUCAUUUGGGGGGGACUAGGAAUUGAAAAUGAUGAAAUUUAAUGCACCAUAAACCCAGAUGUAUUAUAUGCAUAUAUAAUUUUUUGAAGAGUUUUUAAAAGCUGUGCUUCGCAGGGAUGACUGAAAUGCUUGUCUCAGACAACUGAGACCUGUGCAAGGGGAUUGAUCCAUCAGCAUGUGCCCAUGUCUGCUUGAUGGCGCUUAUGUGUGUACAACUAGCUUUACACCUCUCAUGAGAGCCCACAGCUCUUUAAUAAACACCCCAGUGCCAGCCGUGAGGGCUGUGCCAAUAACCACCACUUGAAGCUGGAGAGUGCAGUCUGAGACAGUGAGAUCCUAUACUGCACUUGUAUUUACAUUUUAAGGUUAAUUUAAUUGCAAUGGCUUGUUCUGGUAUGUGUUGCUUUAAUUGCAAAGAAAAAAAAUGAAUUUAAUUUUAUACUCGAGACAUUUCUUUAAAUACUCCUGAAGUUUGUUCUUUAGUAUUAGAGUUCUACAAAGUGAAUUAACUGUGGAGAAUAGCUGUAAAAUACUGAGAGGAGAGGUUAAAUUUUAUAUUCCAGUUUAAGUUAAGGCUAGGAUAAAACUUGUAAACUAUGUUUAUGUAAAAUAUUUUCUAAUCUGUCAAAAAGUUGUCACAUUUUAAUCAAAUUACUUAGUUACCUAAAUUUGUCUAGCCAUAAAUAAGGAAAUAAAUGAGAGGGAACAAGUUUAAUUUAUUGAUGAAGCACUCUGAUGAUUUUUUUUACCCUUAUAGUAAAAAAAAAAAAAAAACACCUUCAAACUUACAUCCUACCAUAUGUUCACCAUCAAAUCUCAAGUCAGAAUCAGGUUCAAAUCAGAAUUCAAAACCAGUUUUAGAACUCAAGUGGCAGCUCAUGCCCUGCAUGCAGGCAAACGGCUAGGAAUUAAUCAGAAAGUUCCACCCAUGUCCAUCCUUCCUCUUACUUGCUCAUCUUCCCAGCAAGCACUAAAAAGAAAAAAAAAAAAAGUACAAAUUCGUACGGAACCUACUGUAACUCUGAUUAAAGAGAUCCUGUAUUCCCCAAUGACCGACCCCCUAGCUCCCCCAAAAAGGAAUUAAACGGCUAAGCUUUUUAUAAAUGUUUUUAAAAUCCUUAUUGGACUUGACAUAAACAUGCAGAUAAUUCUACUAGUCUCUUUUUCAUAGGUACAAUAAUAGCACUAAGUACAGAAUUCCCCUUGUAUCCAAGCAAGACUUUUACGAAAACUUAAACCUGAAGUCUUAUGCAGUGCACCUAAAAUUAACCAGGAGCCUUGGUGCAUAUACCAGCAAAUGUUGUACACCUGUGUGAUAGUGGUCACCUCACUUAACCUCUCCCAGCUUCAGUUUCUUGUCUUUACUACUACAUAAAGUUGUUGAAAGGAUUAAAGGAGACUAUAUAAACAGCUAUUUUUAUUUAUGAUUAAAUAAUAUCUGUGUGGUUACUAUUUAGUCUGGGUAACUAAAUAGCUGGGUUUUUUUGUUCUUUGUACACAUGCACAUAUUCCUUUUUUAAAACAGGCAUAUGGGCAAAUACAUUUUUUUUCUAUAUGCCUCCAUGUUGUUUCUCUGGAUUUCCGCCAGGAUGGGAUGUGCCAAUUAUGCACGGAAUUGUUUGCGUGUCCAUGGGUGCUUAUAUAAGUCAUUAUCUUUGGUGUAUGACAAAUACACAAACUCCUGUAUCUCUAGUAGCCUGUAAUUCCUAAUUGAGGGACAUGAUUGAAUUUAUGUAGUUUAGCCCCAAGUAAGUAGAUAAAAAUUAUUAAGUAAAUGCCCUGGUUCAUCUAAACAAAAUAUGUGACUAAUAGCUUUUUAUAUGAACUAUAUACAUUUAGUUUACCUAAGUUUAUUAAUAAAUAGUAUCUCUGGGCAUUUUUAAUUUUAUAUUUUAUACUUAACUAUGAAAGUAUCCAGAACCAGAUUCCAGUCACUAACUACCUCUUCAUUAAUGGAUCAAUGGUUUUAUCAGAUUUAUUAGAAAUUUGUCUAUACUGAGCAUGUAAUAUGUACUUUGUGAAAAUAGGUAUAAAACUGGGCUCAUCUUAUCAGCAUACCAUUUACCCAAUUAUGGGAGUAAAAAAGGAGGCAUGUGUAUUUUUCCCCUAAUUCUGAAAUGUCUCCCAGUUCUUGAAAUUUGAAUGUGAAAAUGUGUGCAUGCAAAUUAAGACAUUCAAUCUGAAAGACUUCUUUGUAUAAAAUACUAACCAAAUUUAAAGUUGAACCAUAGGGUAAAUAUAGUAGAAAAGUAUAUUUUGAAUUCUGAAUUUUAUUUCCAUUGGAUACAAACAAUAAUUACAAUUGCUAGAUGUGUUUUAAUGAAUAGUUUGAACUCAUCAUGCUAGCAAAAAUCAUCUGCAUAUAAAUAAUAGGGCAAUUUCAAGCAAUUUUUUCUUACUUAGGUCAGAUAUUCCUGCCAGAAACUUGUUUGCUUUGUUAAUUUGUUCAAUUAUUAAACUUUGAGAGUACAAAGAUAAAUUUACUAAUGGGGUUCAAUUAACAAAUUUCUGAUUACAUUUCCCUAAUGAUGAUAGUAUAGAACAUUUAUUUCUGCUGUGCUUUAUUAGUAAAAUUGCAGUGAUCUGGUGACUGGAAUUAAACUGCUGAAAAAUGACUUGGUCUGAUUUAUUCACUGAGCAAAACCAAGCUUUAAAGGCUGUGUUGCUAUGGCACCCAAGAUUAACUGUUAAAAAAAAAAAAAAGUUUAAUUUUAGUAAAAACAUUGGUACAUCUCUUUUGGCAUUGUGUAGAUAAAAAUAGAUUCCCCCCUCCCCCUUUUCUUGUCUUUUUUAUGUUUAGCAAGUCCUUUGCAUUCUUUUAAACAUACACUAAAAGAAAUUUAGCAUAUUUAAAGAGAAGGGAAAAAGCAGUAAAAUAAAACUGUUUUAUCAAAAGAUUACAAUUUGUAAAAUAGCAAAUAUUUCAGUCAUCAUUUUUUAUAUGUAUAUAUAUAUACUUUUUAUUUUGUCUAAUUUAAUCCUUUCAAAAACUGUCUGGCUUCUCAUACUUUUUAGAAAGAUGGUGCCAGAGAGGGAGAAAUCACUCUAUUCUGGUAGUUUCGUUUUGUAAUUAGUCUUCAAACUUAAAAACAGGUUGCAAAAUUGGGACAGUAACAAGUUUUAGGAGAAAUCUUAAUGUAGCUCUAAUCUUUCAAAUUCUAAAAGAAUAUGUUUUCUGUUUCGUGAGACAAAAGAAUUGUCUGGUUGCUUUAGCCAGGAUUGAUUUCUGUCUUCAGAACACCAUUUGGUGGUGUUAAGACUGCUAGAUGAAGAAUUUUGUGGGAAAAAAAAAAAAAAAAGAAGAAAAAUUGAAUGCUUUGUAUGAUCAUCAAAAGCCACUUUUCAGGAGUAUUUUACAUUUCUUGGUGCCAAGCAAAUCAGAAAUCCUACCUUACAGAGAGCGAUUUGUUCAUGAGAUGACCCAGUGCUGCAAGUCGCUUAUGUUUAUCAUUAUGCUUCCACAUUCUAAGGAAAUUCCACUUUCAAACGUUGCCGUCAGUGCUUUCUUCUAUAGGAAGAAUUUGAACUAUAAAAUUUGAGAAGCUUCAGCGUCUGUGGAAAUUUGAGAGCAUUGCCUUUUUUCCUCUUUAUUGAAUGUAAAGUGUUUUAACAAAAGCAUGGUAGCCCAGUACAUUUUAAAUGUCAAAACUUGCACAUAGUGUAUCUCAUAAAGAAUUUAAAUUUUAGACUUUGAACUUUUAAAGCCUCAAACAUCUUUAGAGGCUGACUACAGCAAAUAAACAGAAUGUUUUGCAGAGAGAUUUAGUGAAGAAAAUUUUUUUUUGCCGUUGUUUCUCACAGUGCUCUGCAGGUGAAAAUGGUGAGGAAACUUUGAUAGUUCAAGACUAUGCAGGGGAGAAUUUGAAAGCAGAAACAAGCUUUUACAGAUUUUACCUGGAAAAACAAAGUGGUUUAUAUGAGGUGCUAGUUCUUACCUUUAUGAUUGCUAAUUUAGAUUUUAUAAAAAUUGAAAUGAGUUAAUAUUUUAAAAUAUUUAAGUAUGGUCUCUGGACAACAAUAAGCACAGUGUACUUUUUUAAAAAGUGACUUUAUGUAAGAUUAUAAAUUACAGAAAUGAGUUGUCACUUCCCUGUUGUUACUUAUUUCUGAUUUUAAAAUAGCAAAAUUUAUAAAGCUAUAGUUUUGAGAAAAUAGUAAUUCAUAUUCUUAAAAUUGUUAUAAUCUCUAAAUUAAUACAUAAAUUAUUGAUUUAAUGUUAAAUUUUGAUUUUAAAAUUUAUUUCAGUUUCUAUAGGUAAUAUAUUGAGGUUCUGACAAUUUUAUAUUAAUGUAUGAUUUUAUUCUGACACAGCUGUUGAAUUUGAACUACUAAUUAUUUCUAAGAAUUUGUUAAUACCAUUCUCCAACUUUGUUUUAGGCAGCUAGAUUGUAUCCAGGGAAACCCAUUUAGAUCAGAAAUAACAUUUCGUUCUAACUUCAAAAAAUAAGCAUCCACUUUAAAAAUGGAAUCUGAAUUUAAAUAAAAAUCCUAAUUUAGGAUUCAGUUCCAUUCUUUAACUAGCGGAAAGAAAUCUUAGCAAAAAAAACCAAAAAAACAAAAAAAAACCAAAUUUACCAGAUUGCCAGUAAUUUGCAUUAAGGAGGAAGAGAUGGAUUUUUUUUUAAGUCAGCAGGCAUUGAAGAUAGUUCAGUGAAGUUAAGUAAUAGAGAUCUCAGAUUUUAAUUUAGUCAAGAUUAUGAUUUUACAUAGAAGCACUGUUGAAAUAGGCUUGAUAAUAAUAUUUUAAGUGUUAUACAAAUCUGGAUGAAAUUAUAUUAUUUACUGUCUUACUCAUUGGUUCAACUGUGUUUUAAAAGUGAGAGACCUUAUAUCAAUGAGUGUUUGUUCUGUGCAUCUCAUGUGCAUGGUGUUAACAAAAUAAAAUAAGCAUACUUCUAACAUUUGGGGGAGCAUCCUAUUAGUUUGGGGGUAGGUUAGGGACUCUGCUUUCCAAAUAAUUAAUUUGAUAGAUCCAUGCUCUUGAAAAAUUGGGUACAUACUAUUUUUAAACUUUAUUUUUCAAACAUGAUAUGUAUUGUUUAAAGCAUUAGCUUAAAUGAAAAAUAAUAUUUUACAUUCGUAAAGUUCUGUUUAUUUAAUUCAGUAAUGAAAUUAAUUUGGAGUUGUUGGCAUACUGCCUUCACAGGUUUCUGUGACUCAUUUGCUGAGAAAGUGUGAUUCAAGAGACCAGAAUCAUUUUUUUCUCAUUUGCUAAAACUCAUGUUUUGACUAUGGGCAAAUGUUCAUGGCAGAUUUAAAACAAAUUUAAAGUAAAUAUUCUGUGAUAAUAUUUGGAAGCUGAGUGAUGUCUAGCCUUACAUAACUAGGACAAAUAUAAAUCUGUGAGUUCACGGACUUCAAAAGUAUCAACUAUACAUCAUUUUAGAAUACUGGUUUUGUUUUUCUCAUAUUCUUAGAGUUUAACUCUUAUACUACUAAUUAUGACCUCUAGAAGGUAAUUGCAUUUAGAAGCAGAAUAUCUGCUGUUUUAUUAAUUUAAUAAUUAAGGACUAAAUGGUGUUCCAAUUUAGGUUUAAAAGUAAGCACAUUCACACAGCAUUUAAAACUAUUUCUUAAUGUUUUUUUCCUAGAGAAGAAAUGAUAGCUCCAUGAUCGCUAUAUGUUCUGUUCAAUACUCAUUAUAUUUAUAAUUUAUAUUACAUAUAUAUUUAUCCAUUAUAUUUAUAAUUUAGUCCUGUCCAAAUAAAAUAUAUUCUCAUAGUUAAGUGUGUUGUGGUAGUAUAAUGAUUACAUGAAAUAACCUGGACCUUGCUGUUUGCAAAGUAAUUUAAAUGUUUAUUUUCUGAGUUGCUACUUGGAAAUUAAGUUGUGGAGUGAUGUUUCUCAUUGGUCCAAGGAGCAACAUAAAAUCCUGAUUUAUCAGAUAAUCCUACAGGAAACGUAUGCCUGUUUUGACUUAUGAUAUGUUUCUUAGUACAAUGUCCUGCUUUUCUGGCUUUCCAUUAAAUGUUUAGAAAAAUUAGUUAAUAGUUUUGCAGGAAAAGAAAGGAAAUUUAUCAGUCUAUACCAGCUAUAUAAGAAGUAGGAACAUAUAUAAAAGACCUAUAAUUUUCCGAUCUCACUUUGAACUUUUCUUCACAGUUUUCCAACUCAAGAUGGUAUAUAGUCUUGCACAAUGGGCUGUAGCCAACUUUCCGUCAGAAGAACUGAGUAAAAAUUAUUCCAAAAUUGUUCUUAGAAAUAAAUCUGAGCCUGGAAUUGUCUUGCAUUAAAAAACAAAAAGCAAAUGAUUGCUUUAAAAGCACACCAAAUGAUAUUGGAUGGUCUUUAUUCUUGACUCUGUUUUUUAAAGUGUGUAUACGUUCAUUACAUCCAGUUGUCUAUUGGGCUUUUUUACUCUAACUUUUCGGAAGUUGACUGACAGGCCACUUUUCUAUAGUGGGAAAUAGGCACCUUGUGUGCGCGGAGGGAUUUCCAGCCCCCGACCCCGGAACCAGCAAUUAGCGUUUAGGCGUCCUGCACCCCACCAGGGGGCAGCACCGGACACUGCCUUUCCUAGAGGCCUGAGUGCAUUUAAGGCUUUCUGGCAGUGCUCUCCACCCCUCUUCCUCAUACAGGCCUUACGUAUUUUUGGUAUUUUCUUACACAUUUUAGGCUUAGUAAGUGUUUAAUAAAUGUUAGCUGUUUAGGCAUUGUGCUAUACGGAUGCUACUUUUCAGGUUUGACCGUUCUGUGUACCUGAAUUUUGUCUUUAAUGAUAAUUUGUUCUAUUAUUUAAAAUACCUUGUGCUUAUUAUAAAUAUGGGAUUCCUUUAACUUGUAAAAUCUAGCAAUUAUUGAGCACUAUGACAUGUCAGGCAUGAAACCAGGUACUUUUUAUAUGCUACUGCAGAAUCUAAGUAGACAUAGAGGCAAGAUAACAAUAGAGUCAUAAAACAAUAUGAAACUGCAAUAAUGGGGAAUUGUAAUACUUCUAUUUUGAUGUUGAAUAAACAGUAUAAACCUCGGGGAGGUUAAGUCACAAUGGAACAAAGAUCCCUUCAGAUAGAAUUCCAAAUUCCGUGCUGUAUCAAUUAUAUUAUGAAACCUUGCCAUAAAAAAAAAAAUUGUUGAGGAUGAGCGAAGCCACGAUGUGUAAUGCCUGAGACAGAGGUUUCAGUGAUGUAACUCCAGUGACACUGUGACAAGGAGAAUUAGGGAUUGACAUACUUAAAACUUGAAUGGAGAAAUAGGGUUAGAUAUUGAGAGAUCCCAAGGAAACCUGUGAAAACCUUAAUAUAUGUGUUUUUAUGGACACAUAAUAUGUAACAUAUUACAUUCAUCAAAACAUGGGAAUAAAUUGACGUACUCUUAAUUUUUAAAAGCCCCAUAAAUAUAUUUUACUUAAAACCGUAAUGGAUCUUAUUCUUUUAAUUUGUGCUUGUCCUCUCUUACCUGCUAGAAAAUUUAAAGGUUGUCUGUCCUUCCUAAUUUUAACAAGAUACUUCAUUUUCCAAAAAUGAAACAAGACAAAAAGGUAAAUUUGUUUUGUUUUGUUACAGAAAAUAGUCAAAUGAAGAUAUUUUGCCUGUGUCUGUGACUUUAAUGAUUUGGAAUUGUUAUUUCACAUUGUUUGCUUUCUUUUCUGGCUAUAAUGUGCAUAGCAAUCCAGAUGGCUAAUAUAUAAACAAUUGGAGUUAUGCUUAUUGGAAUCAUUUAGUGUGGCUUAGGAGGUUCCCACUACCCAGGACCAUCUGUUCAUUGCUCUGUGUAUUACCUUCAUGAUCAAGUUUGUGUUUUCAGCUCCUUCACAUAUCUUAGCCUACACCUUUCUUUAUAUGUGAAAGAGGCUUCUAAGACUGAACUUAACUCAUAUGGCCCUCAAGGCUAUAUUGUCAAACCUUGAUAAUCCAAGCCUGCCUUCCACAUUACCAUUCUUCUUUAUUCCUAAUUCAAUUUUUUCCCUUAUCAUUGCUAUUCUCAAUAGUAGGGUCUUAAAAUUUGCAGAAGAGUGACUAAGAAAAUGGGCUUUGUAGUCAGGUUCGAAUCUUACUUGGCUGUGUAUGUAGCGAUUUGAUCUUGGGCAACCUCCUUUAUCUUGGUUUCCUCACCUGUGAAAUGGAGUAUAAUACUGACUUCAUGGAUUUGUUAAGAUGGUUAAAUUAGAUAAAAUAUAACUCAUUUAGCCCAUGCCUGGUUUAUUAUUAACAUAAUUUAGAAUGAAAAUUCUCCUGUUGCAAAAAGGCAUAUUCAGAAGUAAAUUCAAAUACUAUAUUCUAAAAUUUCACAGCGUCUUUUGGAAGAAAUAGCUACUUUUCUUUAAGCACCUGUCAUAUGUGCUUUCACAUUGCCAACAGAAUAUAUGUAGGCGGUACUAAAUUGUUGUUUUGGGGUUCAUUUUCAGUCCUUCUUACUGGAUCCUGGGUGCAACUUUAGACCCCAAGUAGCUAGAGAAAAGUUUCUCUAGGUGCCUGUCGUCUCUGGUUACAUGUUACACUAUAAUCUGCUUUGGAGCCUCACAGCCACAUAUGUUAUUGUUCCACGUGAACUGAGCCAGCUUACAUACACAGCUCUGUGGGGAGAAAGACCAUAAACGAACACUCCCCGUUUCUAGCCCAUAUUCUGCAUAAUACAUGUAAGUCUCUCAACAGCCCUGUAGGCUAUGCCAUUACUUAAUUCCCAAUUUAUGUGGCUUACUUUUUCUGAAUGAAAAGUCAUCAAAUAUGGUUUUUAAGUUAUGGAACAGAAGAAUAUGAUUAAUCUGAAUUGUCAUGAAAAUUCAGGGCACAUGGUUGCUAUGGUUAUGGCGUCAUGUAUUUAUAAUGGAGAGAUACUUUGUCUUCAUUAAUCUACAAACUUGCCAGUGGGAUUCGGUAUUUUUUUUCUGUGUGUGUGUGUGUGUUUGUGUGUGUGUGUACAUACGUACGUACGUACAUGUAUACAGCUUCUGCAUGAAAACACUGAGGCUGAACAAGGUGUUCUGUUUUGGUGGUAGUGCAGAGAAACAUACUCACACAUAAAUUAUUUAUAUGUGAACCAAUUCAGUGAGAAGUAAGUACAGCUGCUUAAUUGACCUAAGGGUCUUAUUUCCAACUGCUUAAAAAUAAGUGUAAAGUGAAGUUCAUGGAAGAAAUAACUUAAGGCUCUUUAAUAUACUUUUGUUGGUGAAGAGAAUUUCAAGCUGUUUCAGUCAGUUAGCAUAUAUUCUUAAAAAGACUGAUAUCCUAUUCGUAGUCUUCUCUUAUAUAUCCUUGAAUUAUCUUCCAUGAUUUUUAUAUUUUAUAUACUUAUAAUAGCGUAUUAUAACAACUUAAUGCUACAUAAUUUACAGUAAUCGUUUCCAAAUUAAGGAAGCCCUAUGUGUAAAAUCACAAAUUUAUGUAACAUAACACAGGAACUUUUAUUCAUAUAAGAAAAUCAUUAUUCACUUUACUGUUUUCCUUUAUUUCAGCAUCAUUUAUUACAAAAUUAAUACUGUUUUCGAAAAACCAAAACAAUAUAUUAUAAAGCACAACGUGGAGUCUUCUCUCACCUCCUUGUCAUUCCCAGCCUCAAAGGGUAACCACUGUUUACAGUUCAAGUGUGUCUUCACAGCAGAUGUUUUUCUAUGCUCGUGCAGACAUAUAGAUGUAUUCCUGGAAAGAGUGAUGCUUGCAUUCUUGAGGAGUUAGGAGCAUUGCUAUUUGAAAAAAUAAAAAUCCAGUUUGAUGAUGUUAGUCAUUAUGCUGAAAGGAGUGAUUUUAACAAAUACCAACAGAACUUCUUGUGGUAGGCCAGCUUUCCAAGUUACUGGUUCAAGAGAACAGUCAUUUUAUAACAGGUAUAAAAUCAAAGACGUUUAGUAAAAUAUUUUGCCCUUAAUUCUCCAUGGAUAGCUUGUUUAUGAAGAGUUCAGUAUUCAGGGAAGAUGGAAAAACAGCCCAGUGUCAGCUAAAGUAAUAAAACCGACUUAAUCCCAAAUUGACAAUUUAAAGCCCUUUAAAAUUACUUGUUGCAAACAAGAAAUAAUCCACCCAGUCUGUCAUCUCUUUUCAGCUUAUUAGUAGUGGAAUCUCUUAGGUGGCUCUUUAAACCGUGUGUAUUAAAAGUCCUAAAGUUGUUCGUGGAGAUUUCCAGUUGCUAGGGAAUACCAACACUUAUUUGGUGUUUGAUAUUGUAAAUCAUGAUAGUUAUUGGGGCCAAAGGGAGGUCUGUAAAUGUCCAGUAGGUUCUCUUUGGAGCUAAUUUGUGCUGUUUGCAUUUUCUUUCUGCCCCAAUACACUUGUCACUGGAAGAAAUCACACAGGGGGUAGGGAUAAAGCAUGAGGUAUCAUGAUUCCUUCAUGUAAAAAUUUUGCUCAAAUUAAAAUGUGAACAUAGUAUAAUAUGUAAAAAAAACUGGACCUCCUUAAAUCCUUUAUAAAGCAAGGCAAUGUGUAAACACAUGAAUAAAUAUGAAGGUUUUAUUUUAAGUAAUAGCUGUGAAUGUUAAAAGUAAUAUUAUUUUCCUUAGAAUAGUUUAAUCACAUAUCCCUUUUAAAUUUUUUAAGCCUUUAAACGUUUUAUUUUCAGUCUGGGCUUGGGGACUCACACCUGUAAUCCUAGCAGUUUGGGAGGCUGAGGCUAGGGGAUCACUUGAGCCCAGGAGUUUGAGACCAGCCUGGGCAACAUAAGAAGACCUCAUUUCUGAAAAAAAAAAAAAAAAAAAAAAAGAAAGGGAAGAAAGGGGAAGGAAGGGAAGGAAAGGGAAGAAAAAAACGAAAAGAAAAGGAA